GGACUCAGAACAAGUGUUACUAAGCCUGCAUUUUUUUAUCUGUUCAAACAUGAUGUGUUUUCUGCUCAUCAUUUCAUCAAUUCUGGUAGUGUUUGCAUUUGUUCUUGGAAAUGUUGCCAAUGGCUUCAUAGCCCUAGUAAAUGUCAUUGACUGGGUUAACACACGAAAGAUCUCCUCAGCUGAGCAAAUUCUCACUGCUCUGGUGGUCUCCAGAAUUGGUUUACUCUGGGUCAUGUUAUUCCUUUGGUAUGCAACUGUGUUUAAUUCUGCUUUAUAUGGUUUAGAAGUAAGAAUUGUUGCUUCUAAUGCCUGGGCUGUAACGAACCAUUUCAGCAUGUGGCUUGCUGCUAGCCUCAGCAUAUUUUGUUUGCUCAAGAUUGCCAAUUUCUCCAACCUUAUUUCUCUCCACCUAAAGAAGAGAAUUAAGAGUGUUGUUCUGGUGAUACUGUUGGGGCCCUUGGUAUUUCUGAUUUGUAAUCUUGCUGUGAUAACCAUGGAUGAGAGAGUGUGGACAAAAGAAUAUGAAGGAAAUGUGACUUGGAAGAUCAAAUUGAGGAAUGCAAUACACCUUUCAAGCUUGACUGUAACUACUCUAGCAAACCUCAUACCCUUUACUCUGAGCCUAAUAUGUUUUCUGCUGUUAAUCUGUUCUCUUUGUAAACAUCUCAAGAAGAUGCGGCUCCAUAGCAAAGGAUCUCAAGAUCCCAGCACCAAGGUCCAUAUAAAAGCUUUGCAAACUGUGACCUCCUUCCUCAUGUUAUUUGCCAUUUACUUUCUGUGUAUAAUCACAUCAACUUGGAAUCUUAGGACACAGCAGAGCAAACUUGUACUCCUGCUUUGCCAAACUGUUGCAAUCAUGUAUCCUUCAUUCCACUCAUUCAUCCUGAUUAUGGGAAGUAGGAAGCUAAAACAGACCUUUCUUUCAGUUUUGUGGCAGAUGACACGCUGAGUGAAAGAAGAGAAACCCUCAACUCCAUAGAUUCACAAGGGGAGCAUCGUGGG